CUUGUUGAUUCUGGGGAGCCGAGCGCGCGGCGCGAGCGUCACGCCAGACAGCGGCCCGCGCGCCUUCUCCUCGGCGUCGGCCGCCGCCGCCUCCCAGAACCUCCUCGUGCCCUCGCGUGCCAGGCCCGCGGCGGCCGAAAUCCGCGGUUCACAGCAUGUCCGCCUCGGCCCCUGCUGCGGAGGGGGAGGGAACCCCCACCCAGCCCGCGUCCGAGAAAGAACCCGAAAUGCCCGGUCCCAGAGAGGAGAGCGAGGAGGAAGAGGACGAGGACGACGAGGAGGAGGAGGAGGAGGAAAAAGAAAAGAGUCUCAUCGUGGAAGGCAAGAGGGAAAAGAAAAAAGUAGAGAGGUUGACAAUGCAAGUCUCUUCCUUACAGAGAGAGCCAUUUACAAUUGCACAAGGAAAGGGGCAGAAACUUUGUGAAAUUGAGAGGAUACAUUUUUUUCUAAGUAAGAAGAAAACCGAUGAACUUAGAAAUCUACACAAACUGCUUUACAACAGGCCAGGCACUGUGUCCUCAUUAAAGAAGAAUGUGGGUCAGUUCAGUGGCUUUCCAUUUGAAAAAGGAAGUGUCCAAUAUAAAAAGAAGGAAGAAAUGUUGAAAAAAUUUAGAAAUGCCAUGUUAAAGAGCAUCUGUGAGGUUCUUGAUUUGGAGAGAUCAGGUGUAAAUAGUGAACUAGUGAAGAGGAUCUUGAAUUUCUUAAUGCAUCCAAAGCCUUCUGGCAAACCAUUGCCGAAAUCUAAAAAAACUUGUAGCAAAGGCAGUAAAAAGGAACGGAACAGUUCUGGAAUGGCAAGGAAGGCUAAGCGAACCAAAUGUCCUGAAAUUCUGUCAGAUGAAUCUAGUAGUGAUGAAGAUGAAAAGAAAAACAAGGAAGAGUCUUCAGAUGAUGAAGAUAAAGAAAGUGAAGAGGAGCCACCAAAAAAGACAGCCAAAAGAGAAAAACCUAAACAGAAAGCUACUUCUAAAAGUAAAAAAUCUGUGAAAAGUGCCAAUGUUAAGAAAGCAGAUAGCAGCACCACCAAGAAGAAUCAAAACAGUUCCAAAAAAGAAAGUGAGUCUGAGGAUAGUUCAGAUGAUGAACCUUUAAUUAAAAAGUUGAAGAAACCCCCUACAGAUGAAGAGUUAAAGGAAACAAUAAAGAAAUUACUGGCCAGUGCUAACUUGGAAGAAGUCACAAUGAAACAGAUUUGCAAAAAGGUCUAUGAAAAUUAUCCUACUUAUGAUUUAACUGAAAGAAAAGAUUUCAUAAAAACAACUGUAAAAGAGCUAAUUUCUUGAGAUAGAGGACAGAGAAGAUGACUCGUUCCCAUAGAUUUGAAGAUCUGAUUUAUACCAUUAUACCAGCAAAGAGAAUGUAUUUCCUUUUCUAAAUCCUUGUUAAGCAACGUUAGUAGAACUUACUGCUGACCUUUUUAUCUUGAGUGUUAUGUGAAUUUGAGUUUGCUGUUUUAAAUUGCAUUUCUAUGCCAUUUUUAGUUUAAAAUCUUGCAUGGCAUUAAUUGUUCCUUGCUUUUAUAGUUGUAUUUUGUACAUUUUGGAUUUCUUUAUAUAAGGUCAUAGAUUCUUGAGCUGUUGUGGUUUUUAGUGCACUUAAUAUUAGCUUGCUUAAGGCAUACUUUUAAUCAAGUAGAACAAAAACUAUUAUCACCAGGAUUUAUACAUACAGAGAUUGUAGUAUUUAGUAUAUGAAAUAUUUUGAAUACACAUCUCUGUCAGUGUGAAAAUUCAGCGGCAGUGUGUCCAUCAUAUUAAAAAUAUACAAGCUACAGUUGUCCAGAUCACUGAAUUGGAACUUUUCUCCUGCAUGUGUAUAUAUGUCAAAUUGUCAGCAUGACAAAAGUGACAGAUGUUAUUUUUGUAUUUUUAAAAAACAAUUGGUUGUAUAUAAAGUUUUUUUAUUUCUUUUGUGCAGAUCACUUUUUAAACUCACAUAGGUAGGUAUCUUUAUAGUUGUAGACUAUGGAAUGUCAGUGUUCAGCCAAACAGUAUGAUGGAACAGUGAAAGUCAAUUCAGUGAUGGCAACACUGAAGGAACAGUUACCCUGCUUUGCCUCGAAAGUGUCAUCAAUUUGUAAUUUUAGUAUUAACUCUGUAAAAGUGUCUGUAGGUACGUUUUAUAUUAUAUAAGGACAGACCAAAAAUCAACCUAUCAAAGCUUCAAAAACUUUGGGAAAGGGUGGGAUUAAGUACAAGCACAUUUGGCUUACAGUAAAUGAACUGAUUUUUAUUAACUGCUUUUGCCCAUAUAAAAUGCUGAUAUUUACUGGAAACCUAGCCAGCUUCACGAUUAUGACUAAAGUACCAGAUUAUAAUGCCAGAAUAUAAUGUGCAGGCAAUCGUGGAUGUCUCUGACAAAGUGUGUCUCAAAAAUAAUAUACUUUUACAUUAAAGAAAUUUAAUGUUUCUCUGGAGUUGGGGCUCUUGGCUUUCAGAGUUUGGUUAAUCAGUGUUGAUUCUAGAUGAUCAACAUAAUGGACCACUCCUGAAUGAGACUUAAUUUUGUCUUUCAAAUUUACUGUCUUAAAUCAGUUUAUUAAAUCUGAAUUUUAAAACAUGCUGUUUAUGACACAAUGACACAUUUGUUGCACCAAUUAAGUGUUGAAAAAUAUCUUUGCAUCAUAGAACAGAAAUAUAUAAAAAUAUAUGUUGAAUGUUAACAGGUAUUUUCACAGGUUUGUUUCUUGAUAGUUACUCAGACACUAGGGAAAGGUAAAUACAAGUGAACAAAAUAAGCAACUAAAUGAGACCUAAUAAUUGGCCUUCGAUUUUAAAUAUUUGUUCUUAUAAACCUUGUCAAUAAAAAUAAAUCUAAAUCACUGGUGUUUUAAGUCACUUGCAUUUGAUAUCUUAUAGGUGUAUAUAGCAUUUCCUUAUGGGGAAUAAUUCUGAAAAGGGAUUUUUAAAUUGAUUCAGCCCUAUAACCUAUACAAUUUGGAAUACUCUUUUGUGGUAAUGGACCAUUUUCUUGGAGUGACUUCACAAAACUGAAUAAUUAAGGUUAAUUUUAUGACCAUUUGCUAUAAAGAAGGUAAGUAGUCAUGCAUAGAGUAUUUGGAAGUGAGGAAAUGGAGUUGUUCUGUAUGAAAGUUCUUGAUGAGUACGCACACUUAUUAAAUGGAUGUAUCACCACUACAGUA